GGCCGGGGGGGCCCCGGGUCCCCGUCCCCAUCCCCUUCCGUGCCCUUCUCUCUGUGACACUGCGGGUCGGCGCAGCUGCGGGUGCUCCCCCGGGUGCCCUUGGAGCGUGGGAGCCACCAGGGGAGGCGCCUCAGACCGGCCGAGGGGAGUGGGUGUCCCAGCACACACAUCAAGUGGCAACUUUAUCUCAAGGCUCCGGUAAACUUAAAAGGGUACAUGUCGUAGUUUUCUCUGUGCAGUUUCAGGGACAUGAUGUAGGCUCCAACUUCAUAGGCAGUGAAAGGGGAGGGCAGGCCAAGGAGAGACCAAAGAAGUAGGUGCUAUUUCCUCCUACCUCAAUUCCGGAAUCUACCCCAGUCUGUGCCCAGGCUUCUAGCAUUUGUAUGCACGUGCCCUUACCCACACUGUGCUUUUCUAUGUCCAAGUAGCUGUAAGUUGUGAAAUUGGGUGUACACAAAUCAUAGCUAGAAUCAAAAGUGUUCGUCAAAUGUCCAAUUUGUGCCUUUGCAUACUUUCGACAAAGCUUUGCAGGGUAACCCCUCUCUGGAGUAAAGAGCACCCUCUUUAUUCCCCACAUAAUAUCAUUCCCCACAUCCCUUGGGUGUCAAGUGCCAGGGUCUUCCAUAGUCCUUCUCAAGUUUUGUGUUCAGCUUUUGUAUAGAGUUUAGGGUCUUGGAGGCAUCCGUGAGUAGAUGAAGAAGCCAGAUACUGGAUUACCUCUGAGAACUGCCCCCCUUCUUUGUUCUCCUCUUGGGAUUUCCUGCACACGCCCCACCCUCAGCCUUGCUUACCUGGCCAGGCCCUGGUGCUCAGGUGCAGACAGGCAGAGGCCCCAGCAGGUCAGGAGGCUCCAGCAGGCCAGGAGCUUGCAGCUGCCUUGCUCUGACCUCUGUCUUGUGGGGAACACACACUUUAGCCUGUAGCUAGCCUCUGAGGGAUGUAUGGGAAUCCAUUAGCUGGCACUGGGGUUUUGCAGGGGUGGGACUGGCAGGGAGUCACAGGCUCUUGAGCCUGGGAGGGCUCUGAAUCCCUCCAUUCUGGCUUCCCUGGGGAGAGUCAGCACCCAGGCUGGGAGCACAGAGAGGGUCAGGUUGUAGGUCUCCUGACUCUGUGUGGAAGGGGAAAGUGGGUCUAGGAUGGUGCAUUUGUCCUAGGUGUUUUGUUUGAGUGUGGAGUAGUGUCUGGAGAGGAAAGGAAGUUUCCCCUCAGUGAUGAUUCCUGCAUAGAGGGCAUUGAUGGGGGCAGGUGGGGAGGGGAAGUGUUGAUGAGGCACCCUACUCCCCUCAUGGUCACUCCAGUCCCAAUUUAGGAGCUAUGAGCAGCCCCUGAUCUGUGGCUCAUGCCAGGCUUUCUAUGUACUCUUUUCCCCUUACUGACAGCUUUCCCUGGAAGUGACUUUCUCCCCUCUGCCAACUGACUCCCCACUGCCUCUGGGGAAGGAGACCAGUAUUUAUGGUUGUCUUGUUCCUGGUGAUUUUUUUUUUUUUAAAGUAGGUCCCUUCCACUCUCGUAGAAGCCCCUGGCAGGUGUAUUCUCUUUCGCCACUUCAGUGUGCAGCAGAUGUUUGUUGAGCAAUUACUUUGGGCCAGGCACUGUGCUGGGUGCUGUGGCUAACAGAGUGGAAAUAUGAGUAGGAUCUAUGCCCUCAAGAAACAUAAUCCCACCAGGGAUUUAUGGGGGAGAGAUGGGGGAAGAAGGGAAGUGUGCAGGGCCAGGUCAUUGGGUGUGAACUACCAGAAGGCUGUGGGUGUGUAUGUAAUAGGAUGGCAUGCAGGAGCUCCACAGCUCCAACCUGGAGCCGGACCUUGGAGGAUGGGUCAGAGGAGAGGGAGCCAGCCGGGUCAGAGGAGAGGGAGCCAGCCAGCUCAGAGUCAAGGUGCCAGGCACGUUCAGGUGGUUGGGCAGGGAGGGGAGGAGUGAAAAAGUUGGAGACGAUGGACAGGACCACUCCUGCUACUACUCCUGGGACUAGGAGUUGGCUUGGGUGUUGGUUUGCAUUUGGUAGGUUUGGAGAGGUACAGGUCAAGAGAUACCUGGCAAGCUGCAGUAGAACAGUUCUUGACCAUGGACCUGGUCCCAGGCUCUGCCCAGCUAGUAACGUGCAGCUUGACUUUGGAUGAGUUACCUCCCUUCUCAGCCACCGUGCUGGUCAGUGGGGGUGGCUCUAGGAAUAUUCUCCCCAUCUAAAUCUGGACUAAGCCUUGGGACUUGAUUCCCCUCCUUCUCCCAGAAGGAGGCGCUGUUGCCAGGGCUGCAGCACCCCAAGUCUCCUCCCUUUUCUUUGCUAGCUGCUAGCCUGUGGGGCCCCCAUUCAGCCACCCUGGGGACAGCUGGGAGGACCGAUGGUCCGGGAAGAGUUUCCAGUAUGUGCCAGGUUGAUCCUCUUGCCCCUGGCCUGAGAGCUGGGGGAGCCCUGGGCUGCCCACCCGCCUCCACCGCUUGGCCGCCAGCUUGGCUCCCGUAACUGGGCGGGCGCAUAGCUGGGGCUCAGCGGUGCGCGUCCUGAUAAGGAGACUGCGCCUUCCAGGGCUCUGGGAAGAGGGCCGGGGCACCGGGCAGACAGAUGCGCGCACACACAUAGCGCAGGCACACCGCUAGCGAGCAAAGUACACUGGAACACCGGCACUGAGGGACUCCCACCUGGCAGCAGUCACCUCCGCACCUUCACCGACCACUGCAGGGAGCCCCGGUGACAGAAGACCCCUUCCUGGGCAGUGUGGACCCCUGCUGUUCAGAGCCCACUCUCCAUCAACUUGAGUUGUGGCCUUGGGGCUAGUUUCCUCUUUGGGCUUCUUUUCCUAUAUCUAAAGUAAAGGGUUGGAGGGAAUCUGCACAAUCUGAGGGCUGAUGUGCAGAUUCCAGGCCACACAGGCCUCCGUCCCCUCCCCCACUCUGCCCCAGGCUUGUCUCGGAAACUGGGGUCCUCAGGAGGGGACCCACCUCUUCUGGGCAUGGGCUAGGGGCCUCCUGGCCUCCCAGCCCGUGGGAGUCAGGCCCAACUCUGCCUCCCCCUUGGGUGUCUUUCUGUCCCAGGAAAAGCCAGUUCGCUGAGCUCGGUGGGUGCCUAUGUGGACGGAAAUGUGGAGAAAUACUUUAAUCACAGCUCUAACCUGUGUUUAUAGAGCUCCUUUCUCCUGAAAGUAUCCAUUAACUUCGGAAUAAAUCUCCUGCUCUUUGCUUCCCCACUUUUUUUUUUUCUGUAAUUAUAUUCAGUAAAUUACUAUUAUCCAAAUUGCGCCCGGGGAAGAGAGACAGAGCGAGAGAGAGAGAACUUCUAAACGACUGGAGGAGGCCGCCUAGGAAAACACAGGGUUCCCAGGCCAGGACUAUAGGAAUUAGAAUGGGCUAGAAAGUUUUCCUUUUAUUUGGCCUGGCAUUAUCCCUUUGAAAUGAGAUCAAUUUCAAGUUGGGCUUCCAAGCCCCCGCCCUGCCCGGCUCAGCGGCCCCUAGCCCUGCUUGUCUGCUCCUCCUAGCUCCUCCUGGAGGUGAGGAAGGGGUGAUAAUGUGCAGUUUGCCUCUUGCUGGCGCCAGCCGGCCGCGCUGUUUAUCUGGCUGCCAGGGGAAUCUGGGCAAUUAGGCUCAGGCGGCCUUAAAGUGCCAGGAGCUCCUUUUCUGCGUCUCCCAUCAUGGGGCUUAGGGUUGAGUCUUCAGGUUCUGGGGGCAGGAAGGACGGGCACUCAGGAGGCCCCCUCCCCAUCCACAGCCCCUCUUUGGGAGGGGGGAAACUUGGCAACCCGGGAGGCAUGUGGAUCUUUUCCUAAGCAAGAUGCUGAGCUGGAAAGAUGGGGGUGUAAGGUAAUGUCCCAAACUGAAACUUUGCCAGGCACUGGGAGAGGCUGUGAACUCUUUUCUGGCUUUAGAAUUUAGGUCUAGAUCCCAAAAGGCUAAGUACCCCCUGGGGGCUAACCAGAGGCAUGCCUGGGCUGAGCUGAACCUUCUGGUGCACUGGCCCCUGGCUGACUGCUCUUCUGCAGGAAGUUGGAGGAGAUUCCUGAAGUUGAUUCCUCAGGCUGGAUGUCCAAGGGGGUUGGAGUUUCUGAUGUCUUUCUGUCUCCCUCUCUUUUCUUUCUCUCCCUACCAGGUCCACUUCUUUCAGAGGGGCCUGCGGUGCUCUAAAAGUUCUCCUGUUAAAGUUUAGAGCAAAUUGGUUAUUAUUUUAAAAUCAAUAAAACUUUUAAAAGUACUAAGACAACUUCUAAGAGGGGAGUGGACAGAGGGCCUGGUGGCAGCUCACAGUUUCUUUUCUGACCUUUGGUCUCACCCACCAAGUGUCCCACCUGAGUGCCCACCUUGCCCACCUGAGGUAAUGCCCUGGGGCUCCACCAGUCCAGAUCCACAGGGCGCAGCCAUGUGGGAGUGGCGGCUGAUUGUUACCCAGUAGUGUUGAUAGCACAUUAUUCAUAACAGCCAAAGAGAGGAAGCAACCCAAAUGUCCAUUAGCUGAUAAAUGGAUAAAUGAAAUAUGGUACGUCCGAAGAAUGGAAUAUCAUUCACCCAUGAAAAAGAACGAAGUCCAGCACCAAAACGUGCUACAACAUGGAUGAACUUCGAUGACUUUGUGCCACAUGAAAGAAGAAGCCAGCCACAAAAGGCCAUAUAUUGUAUGAAAUGAAAUGUCCAGAAUGGGCAAACCCAUAGAGACACAAAAAUCUCCGCCACCUCCCUACUCUCGGCUGUCUCCUCGCGACGAGUACAAGCCACUGGAUCUGUCCGAUUCCACAUUGUCUUACACUGAAACGGAGGCUACCAACUCCCUCAUCACUGCUCCGGGUGAAUUCUCAGACGCCAGCAUGUCUCCGGACGCCACCAAGCCGAGCCACUGGUGCAGCGUGGCGUACUGGGAGCACCGGACGCGCGUGGGCCGCCUCUAUGCGGUGUACGACCAGGCCGUCAGCAUCUUCUACGACCUACCUCAGGGCAGCGGCUUCUGCCUGGGCCAGCUCAACCUGGAGCAGCGCAGCGAGUCGGUGCGGCGAACGCGCAGCAAGAUCGGCUUCGGCAUCCUGCUCAGCAAGGAGCCCGACGGCGUGUGGGCCUACAACCGCGGCGAGCACCCCAUCUUCGUCAACUCCCCGACGCUGGACGCGCCCGGCGGCCGCGCCCUGGUCGUGCGCAAGGUGCCCCCCGGCUACUCCAUCAAGGUGUUCGACUUCGAGCGCUCGGGCCUGCAGCACGCGCCCGAGCCCGACGCCGCCGACGGCCCCUACGACCCCAACAGCGUCCGCAUCAGCUUCGCCAAGGGCUGGGGGCCCUGCUACUCCCGGCAGUUCAUCACCUCCUGCCCCUGCUGGCUGGAGAUCCUCCUCAACAACCCCAGAUAGUGGCGGCCCCGGCGGGAGGGGCGGGUGGGAGGCCGCGGCCACCGCCACCUGCCGGCCUCGAGAGGGGCCGAUGCCCAGAGACACAGCCCCCACGGACAAAACCCCCCAGAUAUCAUCUACCUAGAUUUAAUAUAAAGUUUUAUAUAUUAUAUGGAAAUAUAUAUUAUACUUGUAAUUAUGGAGUCAUUUUUACAAUGUAAUUAUUUAUGUAUGGUGCAAUGUGUGUAUAUGGACAAAACAAGAAAGACGCACUUUGGCUUAUAAUUCUUUCAAUACAGAUAUAUUUUCUUUCUCUUCCUCCUUCCUCUUCCUUACUUUUUAUAUAUAUAUAUAAAGAAAAUGAUACAGCAGAGCUAGGUGGAAAAGCCUGGGUUUGGUGUAUGGUUUUUGAGAUAUUAAUGCCCAGACAAAAAGCUAAUACCAGUCACUCGAUAAUAAAGUAUUCGCAUUAUAGUUUUUUUUAAACUGUCUUCUUUUUACAAAGAGGGGCAGGUAGGGCUUCAGCGGAUUUCUGACCCAUCAUGUACCUUGAAACUUGACCUCAGUUUUCAAGUUUUACUUUUAUUGGAUAAAGACAGAACAAAUUGAAAAGGGAGGAAAGUCACAUUUACUCUUAAGUAAACCAGAGAAAGUUCUGUUGUUCCUUCCUGCCCAUGGCUAUGGGGUGUCCAGUGGAUAGGGAUGGCGGUGGGGAAAAGAAUACACUGGCCAUUUAUCCUGGACAAGCUCUUCCAGUCUGAUGGAGGAGGUUCAUGCCCUAGCCUAGAAAGGCCCAGGUCCAUGCCCCCCAUCUUUGAGUUAUGAGCAAGCUAAAAGAAGACACUAUUUCUCACCAUUUUGUGGAAAUGGCCUGGGGAACAAAGACUGAAAUGGGCCUUGAGCCCACCUGCUACCUUGCAGAGAACCAUCUCGAGCCCCGUAGAUCUUUUUAGGACCUCCACAGGCUAUUUCCCACCCCCCAGCCAAAAAUAGCUCAGAAUCUGCCCAUCCAGGGCUGUAUUAAUGAUUUAUGUAAAGGCAGAUGGUUUAUUUCUACUUUGUGAAAGGGAAAAGUUGAGGUUCUGGAAGGUUAAAUGAUUUGCUCAUGAGACAAAAUCAAGGUUAGAAGUUACAUGGAAUUGUAGGACCAGAGCCAUAUCAUUAGAUCAGCUUUCUGAAGAAUAUUCUCAAAAAAAGAAAGUCUCCUUGGCCAGAUAACUAAGAGGAAUGUUUCAUUGUAUAUCUUUUUUCUUGGAGAUUUAUAUUAACAUAUUAAGUGCUCUGAGAAGUCCUGUGUAUUAUCUCUUGCUGCAUAAUAAAUUAUCCCCAAACUUA